ACCUUUCUAAAAAGACUCCCUGUGGUGUUCAGAAUCACUCCUACAGUCAGGUUCUCCACAAUGGAUCUCAGUGCUGCAAGUCACCGCAUACCUCUAAGUGAUGGAAACAGCAUUCCCAUCAUCGGACUUGGUACCUACUCAGAACCUAAAUCGACCCCUAAGGGAGCCUGUGCAACAUCGGUGAAGGUUGCUAUUGACACAGGGUACCGACAUAUUGAUGGGGCCUACAUCUACCAAAAUGAACACGAAGUUGGGGAGGCCAUCAGGGAGAAGAUAGCAGAAGGAAAGGUGCGGAGGGAAGAUAUCUUCUACUGUGGAAAGCUAUGGGCUACAAAUCAUGUCCCAGAGAUGGUCCGCCCAACCCUGGAGAGGACACUCAGGGUCCUCCAGCUAGAUUAUGUGGAUCUUUACAUCAUUGAAGUACCCAUGGCCUUUAAGCCAGGAGAUGAAAUAUACCCUAGAGAUGAGAAUGGCAAAUGGUUAUAUCACAAGUCAAAUCUGUGUGCCACUUGGGAGGCGAUGGAAGCUUGCAAAGACGCUGGCUUGGUGAAAUCCCUGGGAGUGUCCAAUUUUAACCGCAGGCAGCUGGAGCUCAUCCUGAACAAGCCAGGACUCAAACACAAGCCAGUCAGCAACCAGGUUGAGUGCCAUCCGUAUUUCACCCAGCCAAAACUCUUGAAAUUUUGCCAACAACAUGACAUUGUCAUUACUGCAUAUAGCCCUUUGGGGACCAGUAGGAAUCCAAUCUGGGUGAAUGUUUCUUCUCCACCUUUGUUAAAGGAUGCACUUCUAAACUCAUUGGGGAAAAGGUACAAUAAGACAGCAGCUCAAAUUGUUUUGCGUUUCAACAUCCAGCGAGGGGUGGUUGUCAUUCCUAAAAGCUUUAAUCUUGAAAGGAUCAAAGAAAAUUUUCAGAUCUUUGACUUUUCUCUCACUGAAGAAGAAAUGAAGGACAUUGAAGCCUUGAAUAAAAAUGUCCGCUUUGUAGAAUUGCUCAUGUGGCGCGAUCAUCCUGAAUACCCAUUUCAUGAUGAAUACUGACUGCAGGGAGUUCCUGAACAGAUUUUUCACUCCCACGAGUGCCAAGACGGUGCAAUGGGUAGUCCCCUAGAUGUGAAAAUGAAGAGAGAGGGUUUUACCAUCCUGAGAAGAAAUAAUGAUGGAAACAUGUUUAAUGUUUGUGCAGUGUAAAUGACUUUGACUCAGUCACAUUGAAGUAAAAAUAUUAAAAUCUGUUGAAAUAACUCUUAGGAAAUUAUCAACUAAUUUUUUCAGAUCAGUAUCUUCUAGAUUCCAGACAGAAAAAAAUUACACUUCAGAAAAGACAUCAAAGGCAACAUAUGACAACAAGUAAUUUAUGAAUCUGGGUAGUAGCGUUGGUAAUCUGAGUUCUUUAAGGGUUAACAGGACAACGAAGUGCAUGUGGCAGUGUGCUGGCAGUGGCCUUGAGGCUUUGGACCAUUGGUUACAAAACAGACACAGCCAAGAUAAGAUCCACACACACAUUAUUAACAAGGAAGUGAUUUGCUGCACCUUGAGUUGAGAGGGCUACAUGUAGAAAAGUCUUAAAAUAGAGCUAAACACCACAGUGGUCAACAAAGCCAUCAUAAUGUUGGUGUUUGUUUCCCUCCAAUGUAUGUAUGUUUAGUUUUUAUCCAACCUGAGGAAUGAAAACUUAACUGGAUCUCUCUUGCAUCCUUAAAGGGCCUGAGUCUCAACAUGGCUGCUGAUCCAUACUUACACAUCUUACUGUCAAUCUUGCCUACAUUGAUUAUAGAACCACUAUUACGUGAAAAGGCUUGAAACAACCAACAUAUACAAAUAAAACCCUGCCUUGUAAAAUAGUAAAAGAGAAGCCAUAUAUUGGCUUUUCUUCUUAACUUGGGAGAUAUAUUGAAACAAGGUGCUUUAUAAGAUUAUUGUACUUAAGACUUUAAUAGUGUUACUUGGAUAGCUUAUAUGAAUUUUGAGAAUUUUAUAUGAAUUUUGAGAAAGCAAGUUCAAAAGAACUCUGGUAAUUUUCCUGUAUGUACAAUUUAAAGAGUGAAUAAGAUUAUUAGAAUUCAGCAAUAGAGAUAUAUCUAUUUUCAAUUCAACUACAGAAAUAUAUUUUAUUGGCCGGGUGCGGUGGCUCAUGCCUAUAAUCCCAGCACUUUGGGAGGCCAAGGUGGGCAGAUCAGGAGGUCAGGAGAUCGAGACCAUCUUGGCUAACAAGGUGAAACCCCGUCUCUACUAAAAAUACAAAAAAUUAGCCAGGCGCGGUGGCGGGGGCCUGUAAUCCCAGCUACUCAGGAGGCUGAGGCAGAAGAAUGGCAUGAACCCGGGAGGAGGAGCUUGCAGUGAGCCGAGAUAGCGCCACUGCAGUCCGGCCUGGGUGAAAGAGCGAGACUCCGUCUCAAAAACAAAAAAAAAAGAAAAGAAAUAUAUUUUAUUCAUUCACAUUAGGUCACUGUCAUACUGUCAUAGGAUGAGAGAGUUCUUCAAAAAUUAUGUUUUCCCAAGAUCAGUUGCUUAUAGAUAAUGUUCAAUGACCUCAAGACAUAUAUUUUUGAGAAAUUAUCAUUUUAAAAAAUUUGGUCUAUACUGAUUGUUUUCACUGAUUCCAAUAUUAUUACUUAUAACACUGACCUCUGGAAAAUAUUUUGUUCACAAGAAAUAAUAAAGUAUAAUGAUUUGUUGCAUCA